AGAGGGAUGCGGGCGGCAGAGCUCGAGAGGCGGCUGCCGGGCUGCGGGGCGCCUUGACUCUCCCUCCACCCUGCCUCCUCGGGCUCCACUCGUCUGCCCCUGGACUCCCGUCUCCUCCUGUCCUCCGGCUUCCCAGAGCUCCCUCCUUAUGGCAGCAGCUUCCCGCGUCUCCGGCGCAGCUUCUCAGCGGACGACCCUCUCGCUCCGGGGCUGAGCCCAGUCCCUGGAUGUUGCUGAAACUCUCGAGAUCAUGCGCGGGUUUGGCUGCUGCUUCCCCGCCGGGUGCCACUGCCACCGCCGCCGCCUCUGCUGCCGCCGUCCGCGGGAUGCUCAGUAGCCCGCUGCCCGGCCCCCGCGAUCCUGUGUUCCUCGGAAGCCGUUUGCUGCUGCAGAGUUGCACGAACUAGUCAUGGUGCUGUGGGAGUCCCCGCGGCAGUGCAGCAGCUGGACACUUUGCGAGGGCUUUUGCUGGCUGCUGCUGCUGCCCGUCAUGCUACUCAUCGUAGCCCGCCCGGUGAAGCUCGCUGCUUUCCCUACCUCCUUAAGUGACUGCCAAACGCCCACCGGCUGGAAUUGCUCUGGUUAUGAUGACAGAGAAAAUGAUCUCUUCCUCUGUGACACCAACACCUGUAAAUUUGAUGGGGAAUGUUUAAGAAUUGGAGACACUGUGACUUGCGUCUGUCAGUUCAAGUGCAACAAUGACUAUGUGCCUGUGUGUGGCUCCAAUGGGGAGAGCUACCAGAAUGAGUGUUACCUGCGACAGGCUGCAUGCAAACAGCAGAGUGAGAUACUUGUGGUGUCAGAAGGAUCAUGUGCCACAGAUGCAGGAUCAGGAUCUGGAGAUGGAGUCCAUGAAGGCUCUGGAGAAACUAGUCAAAAGGAGACAUCCACCUGUGAUAUUUGCCAGUUUGGUGCAGAAUGUGACGAAGAUGCCGAGGAUGUCUGGUGUGUGUGUAAUAUUGACUGUUCUCAAACCAACUUCAAUCCCCUCUGCGCUUCUGAUGGGAAAUCUUAUGAUAAUGCAUGCCAAAUCAAAGAAGCAUCGUGUCAGAAACAGGAGAAAAUUGAAGUCAUGUCUUUGGGUCGAUGUCAAGAUAACACAACUACAACUACUAAGUCUGAAGAUGGGCAUUAUGCAAGAACAGAUUAUGCAGAGUUGAAUUGCCUGAGAAGCCCAGUUAUACUGAGGUUACUUGGUAAGCCUAACUAGAGCAUAUAUUCUUUAGAUGUUUAGGGCAUCAAGGCAUCGAGCUAAAACAGCCUGAUGCAAAUGUCAACACAAUAGGGAUUCCACUGCCCUCAAAUUAGGAUAAAUAAGUGUCCUUGGCUAGGACCUCCUCCCCAACUGUCAUAACUUGCUCUAACAUUCUUGACCUGACCAUCCUUGGUCUGAGUUUCCAUUUCUGGGUGGCCUCCCACUCAGUCCACCUGUGUUCUCAGAUAUAGUAAAUUUAAUCAGGAUAAAAUUGAGGCCUGGUUUCACGGAAGCCAUUUCAUGACUUUAAGCCUGAGCUCCUCUGGGAUCUGUAGCUCAGUAGCCCCCAAGAAAUGACCAUUUUAGUAUAUAUCUCAGUCCUUAUUGGAUUGCUAUGUCCUUCUGCAAUGGGAAACCUGCAAAUGUUUUUUCACAAAGUUAACUUUGAAAGGCAUUUUUUAACAUAUAGUUUAAAGUGGUUUGGCCAAUAACAAAGAAAAGUGAAUAUUUUUUCCUAUGGUAGAUCAGCAUUUAUGCUAGCAAAUGCUUUUUAUGGUGACGUUGUUAAUGUUUAACUUAAUAAAACACAGAGUGAAUGUACUAAUUAUCCUGCAUUUCUGCAGAGUUAUUGAUGCAUUAUCAAUGUUUGAUAGCGUUACGUAAUGUUCCUGUAAAAUAUAUUUCACAUGAUUUUCAAAAAAACAAAAAAAAAAAACCUCUGCCUUAAUCUUUCUUUCACAUCUUCUGAGGUUGAAAGCUGUGUGUGUCAUAGAUUAGAAAACUCCCUCCCAAAAGUAUGUCUUUAAAAAUUUCAUUUACUAAUGAAAAUAAAUGUCUGUUUAGCUAAAAAAAAAAAUAGUUUUUAAGUAUUCAUAAAAUGGAGACUAAAAUCAAGCUCCAUUUGUCCUCUAGAAAGUCAGUAUUCCAGAAAGACCAUGUUAUUAGUCUAUAGACUUUAAACGAACAAGCGAUCAGUGCUUUGUCAGGCAGUACACAUCCAAAUUCACUUCUGCAGAUUGGCUGUUCGUGUAAUGUCAAAAUUAUUCUACAAAUCUUGCACCACUGGAUUUUUUCCUAUUUACUUUUCUAUUAUUUAAAGAGCACCAGGGAAGUUGAAGGUUUCCUGUUGUUUGAAAUAAUCUCUGAGCUAUCCUCACACCCCUAGCCACUCACUCAUUCCCUACAGCUGGCACAUAGGCCUUUGUUAUUGAUUUUUGAUUUUUAAUGAAAUAUAGCUAUAGAAGCAUGAGAAACAACCAACAGGCAGACCAGGGAAACUUAUCUGUAAGAUGGUUUUAAUAAAGUGUCCACAUUGUCUUCUAUAUGUAGAAAAAUUAAGAGUAAGCCUAACAUUCCAUCAACAGUGAUAGGCAACUAUUAAUGCUUAUGUGUCUAAGUAGAUUGUCAGUGCUAUAUUCUAAUAUUGAAGCUGGUUGUUUUCUGCAGCUUAACAUACUUCCGAGCUGUUCAUCUUAGCCAUGAAUUGAUACGUACUCAGGAAACAUAGCUAAUUGUAAUGUUAUCCUAAGAAAACCAUUAUCAUCUUCAUUAUACUCAUGAUUAUCAUCAUGAUUAUAAUCAUCAGGAAAAUAAUACCACUGGAAUAGGCUCAUUUUAGUUCAUUCCAAAAUCACCUAGAAAUUAUAUGUGUGUUAUCUGUUGUUUUGGAUUCUCUACAAGGCUAUUCUCCAAUGACAUGGAUAAUCAUAUUUUUAAUUUCACUUGGAUUUUAGAGCCAAUGACUUACAAAUAGCAUUUUGCAGAAGAGCUUGGAGUAGGAUGCAGAACUUUUGACUUAGUCUCAUCUCUGUUCUAAUUCAUCUAAAUUUAGUUACUUAGCUUCUCAGAACCUGUUUUCUCAUCAGUAACAUUUGAAAGUAAGAUUAACCAGCCUGGGCAACAUGGUGAAAUCCUGUCUCUACAAAAAGCACGAAAAUUAGCUGGGUGUGGUGGCAUGCGCCUGUAGUCCCAGCUAUUCAGGAGGCUAAAGUGAUAGGAUAGCUUGAGCCCCAGAGUCCAAGGUUGCAGUGAGCCAAGAUCAUGCCACUGCACUCCAGCCUGGAUAACAGAGUGAGACUCUGUCUCAAAAAAAAAAAAGUAAAAAGAAAGUAAGAUUAUGAUGUUGUCUUUCCAACUUUCGAUGUCUAUAACAAAGUAUAUAGCUUUAGUUCAGAAAUCAUGAUUGAGGGAAAAUUGUUGACCAUCACCUUAUGGCAGCAGUUCUCAAUUUUGCCUCUACCAACCUUCCUCCUCCUCAUUUCCCUCCCACCUCCCAUUCAGGGGACAUUGGCAUUAUCUGGAGACAUUUUUGAUUGUCUGGGGAAGGGGCAGGGGUAAGUACUGCUGGCAUCUAGUGGGUGGAGGCCAGAUAUACGGCUAUACAUCCUACAAUGCACAGGACAACAUUAUCCAGCCAGAAUGUCAAUCGUGUUGUGUUUAAAAUCCUGCUUUUUGGUGCUAGGGAUUAGGGGAAAGUACAUAUUAGAUGAGGUCUAGAAGUUAGGAGGUAUUGUGGAGUCCAGAGUUGGCCUGCCUAAUCAUUCUUGAAUUCUCCCGUUCCCCAAAAGGAGACAAAAUCCCAGAAUGAAGAUCACCAGCUCAGUCAUUUCAUCUUGCUGCUUCAAACACACUUUUUUUUUUUUUUUUUUUUCUGAGACGGAGUCUCACUCUGUCGCCCAGCCUGGAGUGCAGUGACACCAUGUCAGCUCACGGCAACCUCUGCUUCCCUGGUUCUAGUGAUUCUCCUGCCUCAGCCUCCUGAGUAGCUGGGAUUACAGGCAUGCGCCACCAUGCCUGGCUAAUUUUUGUAUUUUUAGUAGAUACAUGGUUUUACCAUGUUGGUCAGGCUGGUCUCAAACUCCUGACCUUGUGAUCUGCCCACGUUGGCCUCCCAAAGUGCUGGGAUUACAGGCGUGAGCUACCACACUCGGCCCCACUUAAAAAAAAAAAAAAAGAUAGUUGUCCCAAAAUAGAAAUGUGAGGUUUCACAAAUAAGAGGCAAUAUCUGUCUCUACAAAGGCUCAUUAGAAUGAUGAAAAUUCAUCUGGCUAAAGAAGUUGUUUUUCUUUUAGUUAUAGGUUAUUGAGGAAAGUCUCACAGACAUAAUUGGAUCGCUUAUCUUAUUCAGUAUUCCUAACUAGUAUUUGCAUAACUUGGGUCCCUGCUUUUCUUCUGUUCAAAGCCAUGUCAUCCUUUUGUUCAUUCUAGCUACUUCUUACAAAUUUUGAUUAAAUUACUGAGCCAAACACUGACUGUUUGAAAGAUUGUUUAAUGAUGAUUUUUAAGGAGGCAACAGCAACCAUUUCAAAGCUUCUUUAUAUCUGGGCACUUCCUCUUUAUACAUUUUUGUAAGCCUUGGCUCAUAGAAAUAUAUUUAAAAACAACUGGCUAAAUUCUAUUAAAACACUCAAUGGCAAUUUUUAAAACUGUUGUGUUGCUCAUGGAACAAAAUGUUUGGCAUGCCAUUAAAACUGAAGUGUUCAUGAAAACUUUCAUAGCUCAAGGAGACGGGGAACCUGAAGAGGUUCUUAAAUGGCAACUUAGUACCCAGAUACACUGUGUCACAUUCUUCUGGGAAGGACAGGAAUGUGCAAUACUGUUAGGUGGCUCCAAGUAACAGACCCUCCUUGGAACAGGAAUAGACCUGAUUGUAUUGGUGUGCUGUCUUACCUACUGAAAUAAAGUUAUUGGUCUUGCAACAAGGACAGUGAGGAUAUUUGUUUAAAAAGACAGCUUGAAAAAAUAGCAAAGACAACAGGAAAUGAUAAACGAGCAAGACUUUGCCACAAUAAUUACUGUAGUAUUGAAACAAAUGAAUAACUUUCACAGCAAUGUUAUUUUCUGUCUUAGAUUACACUACUACCUAUUCAUACAGUAUGUGCACCAUUGCUCUUUUACUGGGAAAAAUAUCUAAGAAGGAGGAGUUGGUUAAUAAGUUGUCUGAUAAAUUUGUGUUAAUGUUUCAGAAAACUUACAAUGUCUUGUGAAAACAGACUAUCUCUGAAAGAUGGAACAGUUGUUUUGUUUUUUAUCUUCACUAGUUUUAUGCUAAAAGUCAUUAAAAGAAAAACUGAGGUAAAUCCCUCUGAUACAGACUGGUGAAAUAAUAUACAAUUAUUUAUAACCUAUUUUGUGAAUGUUAUUCCAUAUGUGAUUUGUUAGUUCCUACUGAAAUGUUUUGGUUUUGUGAAAAAUACUUGGGACAAAUUAUCAAAAAAACUAAAUUCUAUACCUAGCUCCUAAAUUUAUAAAUGUUAUAUAACUUCUCUGAGAAUCUGUAAAAUAUUGUAUCUACAUCUCUUUUUUUUCCUUUUUCCUAUGUUUCAGAUAUUAAAGCCCUUUGUGAGAUAUAACUCACUAUGGAAUUGUAAGAGAUUAUUAUUGACAAAGAUUUAGGAUAUGGAUAUGCCUCAUUCUAAGUGUUUUUCAUAUUGUCAUCAAAUUCAUAUUUUCUAGAUAGAAGUAAUUGUUUCAUUUGGAUAGCAUAAUUUGAUCUAAUCUUAACAAAAUUCAGACUGAAGAUUUUUAAAUUCUACAUUUUUAUUUUCCCAUUUUUGUGUAUCAGUAUAUUAACUGGGUAAUAUUUUUAAAAAUUAGAUGAUAAGGAUGAUGGACUCUUUUUUGAUAUAUGUUAAUAUAUAUAUAAAGCUUCAAAUUUAUGCUCCACGUAGUUCUGUUCCCCACUGAUUGGCUUAAAUCUCAUUCAAACUCCAUUUCCCAAAAGGAUAAGGGCUCUUUGGAGCAACUGUUCAUAUUAUUACAAUGAGUUUUUUUCCCCUCCCCUAAUGGGUUUCUAACUAAUGGACGAGUUUAUUGGGCUCAACAUGUUUAGAAUGUUUCAGAAUGUGUGCACAAAGUAUACUAUGUUAGUCUAAGAUGAUAUUAUUUAGCCUUAGAAAAGAAAUCUAUUAUAUAAUUUGAAUGUAAUAGUAAUGCCCAUUAAAUUUAUGAGUUUAAAAUGUUAAGAGCAUGUUACCCCAUCGUUCCUACAUUUCAUUCCCUCAUUUCAGGGAUUUCAUUGAGAUUUUUUUCUCAAUGAAUAGAAACAUAAACUUUUCUAGUAUCAUCAAAGGAAGGAUUUUACGUUGUAGCUCUUGUUCUCUCUCUGGAUAAACAGAAAGUAAGGAAGUCACCAAUGUAGUUACUGGGGUUCAGGAAGAUUAAAUUCUAACCCCUCCCAUCAUAUAUAUGAGACUUUAUCCUGUUUUUAAAUUUAUUUGGAGAAACUUAGAUUAACUUUGGAAAAACAGAUUUUCUAAGUUUUCUUGAUCACCUAAUCCAAUAGCUAAUAUCCCUUGUAUAAAAAGGAAAUUCAUUUUUUUAAUUAACAAAAUUUUUUCACUGGACUUGAUUUCCAACAGUGCCCUUUAUUACUUUAAAAAGAAAAAUAAAAGAAAAAAAGAACUUACGAAGUUUACCUCCAUAGCUUAUAUUACCUUUAAUUAACAUAAUAUUUUCAGCAGAUGGACUACUAGGGUUUAGCAGAAUACAUACAAACUAUUAUUCGACUUUGGAUUACAUUUUGAGCCUUGAAAUAGCAUAGUUCAUUCAUUGCUGUAUGUGACAUUUUAAAAAGCUGAACAAACAAUAUUAUUCUUGGAAAAGAAAAGUUCUUUCUCACUGGAUUCACCAUUUAGAAACGAUAUUGAAUUGAUUUGAAUCAGAAAAUUGUCUCUAAAAACUUGAAAUGAAUAUAAACAUUAGGCAGAUGAUCUCACCUCUUAUUUCCUGCUUUAGUCCUGUUCUGUUUCCUUUGAGUGGUUCUUAAUAUUCAUUCAAACAUUGUAUGUGUUCAGAUGUAUCCCAGAGCCACAGUUUGCUGUCACUUUUGUCAGAGCCCAGGUUUACUGGGCUCUGUACUUCAGAGCUGUGCAAGGCUCCUAUGCCCUGGGGUAGACCCCUCUUAAUAAGAGGCAUGUUAUAAUCAUUCUACCAGGCACUGUCAUCUUAUAUAUCAAGAGCACUUGCAUAUUUUACCACUAUUUCUUCACCUGUAGAAAGCAUAUGGUGCUUUUAGGUGACUAAAGUUCUCCUGCCUUAGCCUUCAGGCAAAAUUCUUACAUUCCUUGGAGUAACAAAGGUUCAUAUCCCUUUUUGCCCCAGGAGAAAAAAAAAAAAAGGCUAAGAUGCAUCAUUAAUCAUGGAAACUGUCUACUGCAACAGUGCCAAGAAAAUGAUCAUCCUUGUACUACCCAUCAAUAUUCCUGACACCUGUCUAAAAACUCAGGUCAUGCAUAUCCAUCUGCCUUUAGAGAAGUGUCAAUGUGCAAACAUCCUUCCACUAUUUUUAGGGUCAUGUUAAAAUUAUUCACCACCUGCCUGUCAGUUCAUCCAAUUUGUAAUAUUAUCCUGAUCUACCAUUGUCUAUUAUUGGUCAUUCCUCUUUUGCAUUGUGUUUUUAAAGCAUUAGAGUGUAGGAUGUUUUUGAAACUGUCAAAUAGGAGACAGUAGAAUCCUACUGGAGGCCAGAGUUCCCACCAAUAAAUUGCUACACUCGGUGUCCCCUCAUGCUUCAUAGAAUAUGCAGACAUUUCGGACUCCCAUUUCUACUGCAAGCUCCACCUCAAUCUUAUUUCUGGUAAAUGAAUUAUUGUUUCUAAUGACUUUUAUUAUAAAAUCCACCAUAUUUCUAUCUUGGGAAAUUGUUCUAAGAGGUUAAAACACACCUUACAAAUAAACAAAACUUUUAAAAUUAAGGAGUCAAAGAAGAGCUGUUCUGAUAAAACUGUACAUACUCAAAUGCCUAGUAAUAUUAUAUUACAUUCAAAAUUUAAAAUGAAAUGGAAAUUUUGAUAGAAAAAUAUGAUGUAGCAUGAGAAACUCAAGCAAUAUCUUGGUAUGUCUCAUCUAUUAUUCUUAGUAUAAAACUCAUAACUUCUAAAACUAGCUAGUCAGUCAAAUUGUUCACUGGUGUCAAGUCACUUUUUAACAUUUGUAUUUUACAUCUAAUGUAAUUUUGAAACUAGUGUAACUUUCUCCAUGCUCUUUGACUUUUUUUUUUUUUUUGCCUGUUUUCAUUGUCUUGUGCUAACACCUGUGAAACAGGUUAUAAUAUCUUAGAAGUGAGGCAUUUCCAUGUAGAUGGGAAAAUCUCAGAACUGAGAUUUAAUGCACCCUUGGUUCUAGUUGUUGCUAUACACUAAUCCUCAGGAGGAAGACCUGUAUUAGGUAUUACAUUUGACCAUAACCUCCGUGAGUCUUUGUUUUCUUAUCUGUAAAUUACAGAUCUUAGAUAGAUAAUCUCUAAUGUCUGUUUCAUAUAAUAGCCUACCUUUCUAUUAAUUUGUACAAUAAUGACACAUAAAGCCAUGGACUGAAGUGCUCAGUCCUUGGUAAAUAAUGACUUUUCCCAGAAUUUGCAUAAAUAUGGAUAUGGUAGAAUCCUGAAAAUGGGUAGCAAAUUCAGAGUGUCUCUUCAGAAUUGUUGUUGCUGUAGUCAACGUUGCUGGCCCAAACCAUCAAAAUGAUAAAUUGUAAGCCUAGAAAAGUACCAGUGAUUUUCAGACAGUAUCAAGUGACUUGAGUUUAACUGUGACAUUCAUAAAGUCACGUGUCCUGGUUCUUAGGCUUGCUGGUAUCCAGGACUUCAAAGCGGCAGAUAUAACAAAGCAACCUAAGACCUACGAAAUCUAUUCAUGUGGAAGAUGAAGGGGCUUAGGGAGCUUAUGAUUUAAUUAGCUAGUUGGGAUCAGAAUUUUAAUUAGUAAUUUCCUUAUGAGGAUUGAUAAAUGUAUUACCGAUGCUGGUAAUAUUUGUUAUGACUUUUUGGAAAUAAGGAAAUUCAGGGGCAAACUGCACCCAAGCUUCUCUAACUUUAUAUUCAGAAACCCAUGUUACUCAAACAAAUACACAUAUGCCAAAUUAUAAUUAUUCAAAUAACUUUUAUGGCAAAUAGAAAAUAAAGCAUUAAGAAUGCUAAAGUAGAAAUAAUAGAAACACAUUUAAUUUUGCAUUUACUUUGUGUCAUGCAUUAUAUAUACAACACGCUAUCUCAUCUCUUCACAACCUGCCUGGGGAUCAGGUAUAAUGAGGAAAGCAUAGCUCAGAAAUGUUGAUGCAAUAGAACAGGGAUUCCAGCUGAUGUGUGUAACUAUAACUGGCAACAAGGGAAGUCAAGAGUGUUUCAGAAAAUGGUAGUGUUUGCAUUGAGUGUGCCUGGCAGAGAAGAGAAAAAAUGUUAUAGACAUAGGGAACAACAUUUAAAAGGCAAAGAGGCUUCAGUGAGUGGGAAUGCCCAGGGAAUGACAAAUAGUUUCAUGGCUAAAGCAUGGAAUGAAAAAGUGGAGCAACUGGAGCUAAGUGAGAGUAGUAGUUUGUUGCUUCAAUUAAGUCUCUUUCCUCAUUUGCAAUAGAAGUUAAAAUUUAUCUUCUGCUCAAUAGGGGAGUCACUAAGGUAUUUUAAAUCAUGUCGUAUUUUUUAUUAAAUAAAAAAAAAAAACCUGGCAGCAGAGUGAAGAACAGGCUAGAGAGGGAGGGCAUUAGGCAAGAUUAAUUAGAAGACUACGGUCAUAACAAUGAAGAAUGAGUGUUGUGGAUGAUGGUAGCAACAGAGAGAAAUACAUAGAUUUUAGUUGGAUUUAGGAGAUAAAAGGUUACCAGAUUUGCUAACUGACCAGGCAAAGAGAAGUGGAAAGUCAGGAAAAAUACGAAGGUUCCUGGUUCAUCUGGCUGCCUAGAUGAAUGACAGUUCCAUUCCCUAAGAUAGAUAGGGAAAAAAGUAUCAGGAAGAGUAGGACUCGGGGCCAAAUAAUGAAUAUGUUCAUUUCUAUGUUGAUGUCUUCAUCAACAUAGAUGACUGGAGGUCUGGAGAGAAGAGGGCAUGGAAAUGAUUAUGUGGUAACCCUCAAGUAGAGGCAGACGCUGGGGGUGGCAGUGAAUUCAAGUGGAGGAAAAAGCAAAGAUGACCAAAUAAAUACCUGGGUAACCAUGGGGCAAAUAACAAGAAGCCCUGGAAGCAGAUGGAAAUUGUGAAAACACUCAUUAGCUUCUUUCUCCUUUGUUUUCUUCCUUUCUUCUUGCUUCAUGUUUUUCUUUAAUGCCAGAUGAAUAAUGAUUUCACUGUGAGAGUUGUAUUUUAAAAUGUUGUUCCUGUUGCAACACUUAUUUUUCUGUACACUGGGGCCUAACACAAUAUGCCCUGGUUGUUUUCUGUGCUCACAAAGAUGUGCUUCCUCAUCGUCUCCUGGCCUGCCCUUCACACCUUCCAGGGUAGGGCUGCUGGGCCACUCUCUUUCCUGUCCAUGUCACUCCAUGCAUUCUCUCUGCCAAUAGUGUAUUAUUUCCUUCACUGUGUUUAAUGUGAGCAGAUUUAUUUAUGUAUUUAUGCUUUUACCUUUUUAUUUUAUGUCAUCUUUUCUCAUAAUAGAAACUCCAUGAGGGCAGGGAAUUUGUCUUGCUCCUCCCUGUAAAUGCAGUGCCUAAAAGAAUGCCUGACAAAUAGUAGACUCUCAGUAAUUAUUUGUUGAGUAAACGAAUAAGACUGAGAGCUACCUCUCUAGAAACCAAACUACAUAAAAUUUUAAAGGAAGCUCCAUACCAAAUUAAUAUCUCUUUGCUUUCUUCUCAAGAAAUUCUAACCAUACUAAUAUUAUUUAACCAACUUAUAAUGCAAAGCCACAUACAGGUGCUAAAACAUAUAGAUAGAUAGAUAGAUCGAUAGAUAGAUAGAGAUAUAUAUAGAUAUAUAUUAAUCAUAAAUUAAAAAUUUUCACUCCUGACAAAAUGGAUCCUAGUUAGAGGGUUUAAUUUUUUUUUUUUAUCUCUACUGGGCAUUUAAAAAACAUUUUAAGGAAGAACUUGUAUAGAAAAUAUAAUUCCAAACAUUGCUUUGGAAGUAAUAGCACAGCCUGUUUACUGAGAGGGGAAAAAAGAGACCUUCAUAUGCAAAUGUAUGGCAUUUGAAAAUGUCAUAUAGCUACAUCUACAUAUAAAUAAGCUGCUCUCUGAAUUCCAGGGAAGGGGAGAGUUUUGUAUAGCGUUAGCCAAUUUCUCUAUCAAAGUAAAGUAAACUAAUAGAAUAGCAGUGACUCAAGAUAUAGAAAAGCACAUCUUUACUACCUCUUAAUACAGUUGUGGCACUCCAGGUCAAAGACCACCUGGCCAAAAUCCAAACCUAAAUGAAAUCAAAUCCCACAGUGUUUGAAUGGCAAUAGAAAUGAAUCAGCUGGAAGAAAAGGGAUUCACAGAUCAAAAAACUGAGAACUUCCUAUCAAGUAUUUGCUUCCUUUCUAAACAGUGACAUGAAAACCAAAGGCUUCGUGAGGUCUCCUACACUUAGCCUCUAUGCCAGAAUUGUUUUUCAGGUGGGGUCCUAAAGGUUAAGCCAAAAGAAGAAAAGAUUUAAUUUUUACCUCUUUCCUAUUUCAUAUUUGUUUCAUUGCCCAUAUACAAGACGGUCACUUUGGGAACAUUUCUCCGGUAAAUCCUAAUAUGUAAACUACCAUAUAGGGAUAAAUAACUCCUUGUAUUAAAUGAAUUUUUCCUCCAGAAGACCAGAGUACCAUUCAAUUAAACUAUAUUUUUCCUACAUUGUAUGGUUCUCCCAGCUCCUGGAGGAGUUAAUUGGCCUCACUUGAAUAGGCAGCCCAUUCCUGGAGACGAGGUGCCCUGGUAUUAUUUUUACAAUAGGCCAUUUGCUGCUUUCCAAGUUGAGGCUACGGAAUUCACCAUAAGAAGAAAAAAAUCUUAAUAAAUUAUUUUAUGUAAUUUUUACUGACCAUUUCAUGCAGUCCAUGUGGGAGUUAUGUUUCCCUACCAGGAAGAGCUGACUGCAAUCUACCAGGGGUGCCUGCACCACAAUUUCAUUUUAGGUGCUAAAAAGCAUACCAAAGCCUGCCCUGGCCCUUAUAUAGCAUAUUUAUAAGGGAGCUCAGGCUGAGAAAAUAAGCUUCUAGAAUGAUAACUGAAGGGCAAUACUUGUAUUUUAGAGAAAAAGACAUUUUAGUAAGCUUAAGGUAUCAAUGGGGAAGAAAAAGGAAAAUUCAAUAGUCAAAGGAAAGCAAGAAAUCAGGGUGGUCUUCAGAUAGAUCAAUAUAAUUGCUUUUUUUUUUUUAAUAGGGCUGAAUGCUUGGCAAUUUUAUUAGUGCUUCUCUUUGAAAUGACUUUUCAAUGAAAGAAUUAUUAUCACCAUUACAAAGAUAAAGAAAUUUAGGCUCAGAAAGAUUAAGCAAUUUUUCCAAGGCCACCCACCUAUUUAAGAAGCUGAGAGUAUGUAUAAACUGAGAUCCCUUUGACCACAAAGCUGGCCGAUCGCUUUCCAUUAUACCGGCCUGCCUCUCGAUAAAUUGAGUAACAGGGAAAAGGUAGCAAGAUGCAUACUGGCUACAUCCGAAACUAUACAGUCUCUUGUGGCAGAUAUUAAAGGAACCCAAACAAAUCCCUAAUGAGGAUUAAAAAUAUCGUAUCAAAAGAACAUGUUCAGGAAACUAAAAAAGGAAAAAAGAAGUAGAGAAAAUUUUGUUGAGUUUCUGCUAAAAGUGCUGACAUGUGGGGAUAUUUAUGUUUUUCUGAACAUCUGGUGGAUAUUAGUAUGUUUUUAUUCACAAUCUUCUGUUAUUAAUGAUAAAAGCUGAGUAAUUAUGAUAUACUGCCACAAUGAAUGAAUACCAUGCAUUUUUUCCAGUGUAUUACAGAAUCUCAUCAUUCCAUCAAACAUAAAAACAUAGUUAUUUUUGAAAAGAGGAAUAUGGAUAUUAUCUUAUUAUAACAAACUUGUUUCCAUCAGAAUAGAUCACAUUGAGUCAGCAACUCUGUUUCUAAGAGAUGAGAUACACUUCAAGUCAUAAGAUUUGUUGUUAUUAAUAAGUAAUUCAAAUUACAAUUUUAAUAUUGCCUUUAGUUUGAGAAAUGACCUAAACCUAAUAUAUAUUUAUUUUGUCAAGACAAAAAAUCCAUUUCUAAGAUUUCAUGGAAGGAGAGAUUAUUUUAUUAGCAACAGACACACCAUGGCUUUUGUUUCCUUUGUAAAUUGUCAAAAUGAAGUGUAUCUUUACUGACCCUGUAAUCUUCUCCCUGGCUUCUGUCUAGAGCUCCUUCAACUAUGCAAGCCUUUAAAAAAAAUUCAUUACUGAAUACAAUUGACUGUCUUCCACAAAAUGCCAGCAAUGACACACGCUCAGAGGCUAAAACAAGCCUGGCAGUGGGACUGCCCAUAGGUGAGAGCAUAGCAGGUGAUGGUUAGUGGGUGCCGCCUUUGCAGCGGGACUGUACAAUAGCUCCUAUGGCAUGGACCACACUCCUCAAUCCAUGCCCUCUAGCCUGCUCCAGGCACAACUAGUUCCCCCACAAGCCAUGCUCUCUCUCCCGUCUAAGUUUUUUGUGUCUAUUGGUCCAGCAUGGAAUACUCUUCUGCUUUUGUCUUUGGCUAAUUCAUGUUCAUAUUUCAUGUAUCGGCUUCAGAUAGCCUUCCUCUGAGAAUGAAAAUAAUAUAACAGCCACUUUCAUUUAUUGAGCACUUACUAUGUGCCAGGAACUUGGCUAAACAAAGACUUCACAUUUAAAACUCUUUUACUCAUGACACACAUUAGUUUAAAAUAGCUAUAGUUUAUUGAGUACUUACUGUGUGCCAGACAGGCAUAAAGGUUAAUAAGUUGCCCGUGGUCACAGAUAGGAAAAAAGGAAAACAAACGAAAAUAGGAUUUGAACCAAGACAUUCAAACUCCCAAGCCUGUGAUCUUAUUACUUCAUAAGUGUGUAUAGGUAUCUGUUAUUUCACCCGUUUUAAAUGGAGGUCUUCACUCCCCACCUUCCACCCGGAGUCUGGGCCUAAGUCCUGUUGUGUCCAACAUGGGCCUCCUAUCUCUUCCCAGUCAUCACAUUGCAUUGUAUUUGCCUGUUUGCUUUUCAGACUCUUUCUUUCUAGAUAAGGAAACAAAAGCCUUGAGGAAUGAAGGAAAUUGCCAAAAGACCAUUAACAAUAAUAAAUGACUAAGCCCUCUGUUCCACAGUCUGCACUUUUCUUUCUGCGGAAUGACCCUUGUAAUUGUAAGCCAGGGCAUUUCUCCACAGAUGGAUAUCCCAUAAAAACAAAGCCAAAGUGACCUGAAAAGCACAGAGAAAAUGUAUGUCUAUGUCCAUUUCUUCCUUCUCAAUGGUUCCUUUUUAUUCGUUUGAAAAUAAGAGUGUGAAGAUGUGAUUCUAAUGACUAAUAACAACUAAAACAUUUAUUAAGUGCUGAUUAUUUGCCAGCUCUUUUGCUGAGGGUUUUAUAUGGAUCCUCUCAUGUAUUCCUCAUAAUAAACCUGUAAGGCAAAUACUAUGAUUAUCCCCAUUUCACAGAUAAGGAAAUAUCUACAGAGGAGUAUUUGACUUGAUUUGGGCCCCAUAACUAAUAGGCAGAGGCACUGGCUUUUAAACUCAAUUUGACACAAUUACUCUUUAUUUGUAUAAGAAGUGAGAUUAUUUUCAGUAUUGCAAAAAUUCACUGUCAAUUACCAAACUAUUUGACUUAGAUAACAUAUCAAUUAUGUGUUGUGAGACAAACAGCAAACAUACCUUAUGUUCAGAAUCCUUUAGAAAACACUGAGAAAUAUUUAGAGAAUAAGAGAGAAAUGAAUAUGCCUAAAGCUCUCCAUGCUCAUAUUUUGCUCCUGGUUUCUUUGGAAUGUCCUAGCUUGAAGAGAUGAUAAAGGGCUUGUAUGGGUCCAAUUCUGUGUUGUAGAAAGGCAGAUGGGAUCCUGAGGCUCUGUAAAACUGUUCCUCUGCUAGGCAUACUUCAUAUUCUCUAUAUUAAACUCAUCUUUAAUUGGCAUGGAAGAUUCAUUGUUCCAAAUCUCAGAUGAAGAUCCCUAUAUUGGAUGCAAUUAAGCCUGGCAGCGCCCUCAAAAGACAGUCUUGUCACUGCUAGCCACAGCCAGGACACAGUAACAGUUCCUUCUAGUGACCCAAGACCAAUAAAAAAAUAAAACUACUAAAGAAGUUCUGACCUCCAAAGGCAAUUAGCCCAUUCCUGGUAUUGCCAAUUAUGAUAGAAAAAAAUUGCCAAGCUCCUGGGACAUGGAAAUACACUCAGUAACAUUUGAGAACUGGAGAAACUAUUUUCCAAAAUAGUAUGAAGACAUGAAGGUGAUUUGUAGAUAUUUGAGUUUGGAGAAAGUUGAGGGAAAUCAGAUUACACAUGUUUACUACAAGAGAUUGUUAAUAAGUAAAGAAAGGCUCUGAUAUAACAAAUCUAAACAGACGAAGUGAGAAUAAAAUCUUAAAUUCAAAAACUUGACCAUCCCUUUUUAGGCAAAAAAAAAAAAAAAAGAAGAAAAAGAAAAAAAUCACCUGAUGACCUUCAUUUUUCAAUUAUUAGAGUUAUCUCUACUACCUAGAAAUAAUCACUGUCAAAUUUUGGUGAAUUUCCUUCUAGUUUUUUAUAUUUCCUAUAUAUUUUUUUAAUUAGCAUCCUUCUCAUUUUCUAUGUCAUCAAAAUUCUUCAUGAUUUUUUUCUAUUUAAAUAACAUUUUAUCAUUUUGUUGUAACAUUAUUUAACCAUUACACUGUUGUGGAAAAUUUAGGUAAUUUCCCAUUUUUUACCAUUUUGGAUGAUGUUAUAAUUAAUUAAUCUCUUUGUAACCUGAGUCUUUGUGCUUGAGGCUCUUGAUAUAUGAGCUACUACAUUCCUCUUUGAAAGUCUCUACCAUAUUCUUUCCAAUUGAUGGUAUCUUAAAUUUUCUCUGCACCAUUAACCACUGGCCAACUAACAUAAUAAGUGGACUUCCAAAAACUACAAUUCUUCUCCAGAUAGACUAAAUGGUCUACUUACAAUGACCCACACUGAACAUUAACUUCCCUGAUAUUUUAGAGCAGCUUUUAUAGACAUGGCUGGAAAUUAAGCUUACAAUUAAAAAAAAUAAAGAAACAUAAAAAAGAAUGCCAUUUGCAUAAACUAAGCAAACAGAUCCAAAAUAUAUACAUAGUAAAAAGACCAGAUGUAAAUAAAUAAAAUUUUGAUUUUGGCCUUCUUUAGGUUGUGAACUUUCAGUACUUUUGUUCUUUUCCUAUCUAUAUUUUCUACUAUUCUCAAAUCAAUGUGAAUUGCUUUUAUAGCAAAAAAGCCAAUAUACUUUAUUUUUAAGAAAAAGAUAUAUAGAACCAAGCAAUUUAGUCCUCCAAAAAAAAACCACAUUCUUCAUAUUGAAUGAUAUACAGUAUCCUAUUACAGUAGUAUGCGAAACACCUAUAGUUAUGACUGUACCUACAGACUCAACUGAAAGAAGAAGGCAAUCAUAGGAAUCUCUCCAGGCCACACACACACACAAAAAAAAUUCUGUCUCAAUUAUCUAUAGCUUUCACACAAAAUUGUUUUCUGAUCUGGAAUUAUCCAGAUGACUGACUCUUUCAUUUUUCUUCUAACUCUACAUGUAAAACUCUAAGACAAUUAUUUACCACUGAAAAAUUGUGAAGAAAACACCAGAUUAAAAAUGAGAACACACAGAAAAAUUGGGCAUGAGUAUGUAAUAAUUCUCCGUACUUUCUGGGUAUUAGUCCAUUCUCAUUCUGCUAAUAAGACAUAUCCAAGAUUGGAUAAUUUAUAAAGGAAAGGGGUUUAAUUGACUCACAGAUCUGAGCGCUGGGGAGGCCUCAGGAAACUUACAAUCAUGGUGGAAGGGAAAGUAGACACAUCCUUCUUCACAUGGUGACAGCAAGGAGAAGUGCAGAGUGAAGGUGGGGAAAAACACCUUAUAAAACCAUCAGAUCUUUUGAAAACUCACUAACUAUCAUGAGAACAGCAUAGAGGUAACUGCCCCCAUGAUUCAAUUACCUCCCACCGGAUCCCUCCUGUGACAUGUGGGGAUUAUGGGAACUACAGUUCAAAAUGAGAUUUGAGUGGGGACACUGCCAAACCAUGUCACUAUCUUUGUUAACUUUUCUCUAAACCUAAAUCUAUUUUAAAGUAGAUUUUUAGGAGACACACAUGGCUUCUGGAGUUCUCUGCCUUUAGCCCUCUCAUGACAUUAGAGAUUCACUGAAUAUUUCUGACCUCAAGCUCCUACUUUAUCAAAGAAAAAACCGUAUCUAUACACAAACACAUAAAUAUAUAUGUAUGCAUGUAUAGGUAUAUAUAUGCAUAUGUGUAUAUAUGCAUGUGCGUGUAUGUGUAUAUACACACACAUAUAUAUAAAUAUGUAUUCAUGUUCUUAAACUUACAUACCUGUUAGGAGUGUUGCAGUCUCAAACAAAAUAAGAGCUACAAAAACAAAAUUUUAAGUCACUAUAUGAUUAUAAAAUAAUAAUAUUAUUUAAUAAUCUUUUGGCAAGUAGAAAACCUACGUUAUAUAAUGGACAUUGAAGAGACCAAAUCUAUGAACUUUUUAUCUUAAAAGAACUCUUAUUUUCUUGUGAUAAAUUUUUCAAAAAGAAAGCAAAGUUUUGCUUAAAAGCAUUUCUCACUGAUGUUUCUGCAUAGUCUAAUUUUUUCCUUUCACUUCAUGAUUUACUUAUCUUGCCUUUAAAUUUACAUCCCCAAAUUCUUCGUAGACAAUUACAAAUGUCCUUCCUCCUACUUUAGAUAUCACGUAGCUGUAAGUUUUCAUUUCUUAAUCAUACAUUAUCUUACUAUUAUUUAGUAGCUAGUUCACCCCUUAAUAAUUUUCCACUGAACUACGGAUUCUUUCCAGUUAACAUCAAUUCUACUGUAGACAUACCCAAAUAUAAACAUAGAAUUUUCAAUGUAAUCUCAAAAAUCCUAAUAAGGGAUAUCUGUCAUGUUUAUACAUUGGAGCUUAAAUGUUUCUUCUAAUUUUUCCCAUUGUACAAAAUAGCACUACCAAGAUGUUUUAGCCAAAAACUGCAUCAUCUUGGAAUAGUUCCUACCAUUUUGCAAUACAUAAACAGGUCAUAUUCAAUCCACCUGUAAGGUACAAGGGAAAUAAAAGUAAUUUUUUCCCUUCUUCCAUUGCUACUACCCAAGUUGAAGACUGGGACAUUGUCUUUCUCCCACACCACUGUACUGGUCUCCUGUUUGCUCUCCCUGCUUCCUCUGUGUCCCCUUAAUGAUCAAUUUUUAGUAACAGACAGAUGUGCUGGAAACUACCCAAAUGCUUUCCCAUUGAUCUUUAAACUAGGUCAGGCACAGUGGUUCAUGCCUGUAAUCCCAACCCUUUGGGAGGCCGAG